GCCCUGCCUCCCCGCCCGCGCACCCGCCCGGAGGCUCGCGCGCCCGCGAAGGGGACGCAGCGAAACCGGGGCCCGCGCCAGGCCAGCCGGGACGGACGCCGAUGCCCGGGGCUGCGACGGCUGCAGAGCGAGCUGCCCUCGGAGGCCGGCGUGGGGAAGAUGGCCCAGUCCACCGCCACCUCCCCUGAUGGGGGCACCACGUUUGAGCACCUCUGGAGCUCUCUGGAACCAGACAGCACCUACUUCGACCUUCCCCAGUCAAGCCGGGGGAAUAAUGAGGUGGUGGGCGGAACGGAUUCCAGCAUGGACGUCUUCCACCUGGAGGGCAUGACUACAUCUGUCAUGGCCCAGUUCAAUCUGCUGAGCAGCACCAUGGACCAGAUGAGCAGCCGCGCGGCCUCGGCCAGCCCCUACACCCCAGAGCACGCCGCCAGCGUGCCCACCCACUCGCCCUACGCACAACCCAGCUCCACCUUCGACACCAUGUCGCCGGCGCCUGUCAUCCCCUCCAACACCGACUACCCCGGACCCCACCACUUUGAGGUCACUUUCCAGCAGUCCAGCACGGCCAAGUCAGCCACCUGGACGUACUCCCCGCUCUUGAAGAAACUCUACUGCCAGAUCGCCAAGACAUGCCCCAUCCAGAUCAAGGUGUCCACCCCGCCACCCCCAGGCACCGCCAUCCGGGCCAUGCCUGUUUACAAGAAAGCGGAGCACGUGACCGACGUCGUGAAACGCUGCCCCAACCACGAGCUCGGGAGGGACUUCAACGAAGGACAGUCUGCUCCAGCCAGCCACCUCAUCCGCGUGGAAGGCAAUAAUCUCUCGCAGUAUGUGGAUGACCCUGUCACCGGCAGGCAGAGCGUCGUGGUGCCCUAUGAGCCACCACAGGUGGGGACGGAAUUCACCACCAUCCUGUACAACUUCAUGUGUAACAGCAGCUGUGUAGGGGGCAUGAACCGGCGGCCCAUCCUCAUCAUCAUCACCCUGGAGAUGCGGGAUGGGCAGGUGCUGGGCCGCCGGUCCUUUGAGGGCCGCAUCUGCGCCUGUCCUGGCCGCGACCGAAAAGCUGAUGAGGACCACUACCGGGAGCAGCAGGCCCUGAACGAGAGCUCCGCCAAGAACGGGGCCGCCAGCAAGCGUGCCUUCAAGCAGAGCCCCCCUGCCGUCCCCGCCCUUGGUGCCGGUGUGAAGAAGCGGCGGCAUGGAGACGAGGACACGUACUACCUUCAGGUGCGAGGCCGGGAGAACUUUGAGAUCCUGAUGAAGCUGAAAGAGAGCCUGGAGCUGAUGGAGUUGGUGCCGCAGCCACUGGUGGACUCCUAUCGGCAGCAGCAGCAGCUCCUACAGAGGCCGAGUCACCUACAGCCCCCGUCCUACGGGCCGGUCCUCUCGCCCAUGAACAAGGUGCACGGGGGCAUGAACAAGCUGCCCUCCGUCAACCAGCUGGUGGGCCAGCCUCCCCCGCACAGUUCGGCAGCUACACCCAACCUGGGGCCCGUGGGCCCCGGGAUGCUCAACAACCAUGGCCACGCAGUGCCAGCCAACGGCGAGAUGAGCAGCAGCCACAGCGCCCAGUCCAUGGUCUCGGGGUCCCACUGCACUCCGCCACCCCCCUACCACGCCGACCCCAGCCUCGUCAGUUUUUUAACAGGAUUGGGGUGUCCAAACUGCAUCGAGUAUUUCACCUCCCAAGGGUUACAGAGCAUUUACCACCUGCAGAACCUGACCAUUGAGGACCUGGGGGCCCUGAAGAUCCCCGAGCAGUACCGCAUGACCAUCUGGCGGGGCCUGCAGGACCUGAAGCAGGGCCACGACUACAGCACCGCGCAGCAGCUGCUCCGCUCUAGCAACGCGGCCACCAUCUCCAUCGGCGGCUCAGGGGAACUGCAGCGCCAGCGGGUCAUGGAGGCCGUGCACUUCCGCGUGCGCCACACCAUCACCAUCCCCAACCGCGGCGGCCCAGGCGGCGGCCCUGACGAGUGGGCGGACUUCGGCUUCGACCUGCCCGACUGCAAGGCCCGCAAGCAGCCCAUCAAGGAGGAGUUCACGGAGGCCGAGAUCCACUGAGGGCCUCGCCUGGCUGCAGCCUGCGCCACCGCCCAGAGACCCAAGCUGCCUCCCCUCUCCUUCCUGUGUGUCCAAAACUGCCUCAGGAGGCAGGACCUUCGGGCUGUGCCCGGGGAAAGGCAAGGUCCGGCCCAUCCCCAGGCACCUCACAGGCCCCAGGAAAGGCCCAGCCACCGAAGCCGCCUGUGGACAGCCUGAGUCACCUGCAGAACCUUCUGGAGCUGCCCUAGUGCUGGGCUUGUGGGGCGGGGGCUGGCCCACUCUCAGCCCUGCCACUGCCCCGGCGUGCUCCAUGGCAGGCGUGGGUGGGGACCGCAGCGUCGGCUCCGACUUCCAGGCUUCAUCCUAGAGACUGUCAUCUCCCAACCAGGCGAGGUCCUUCCAAAGGAAAGGAUCCUCUUUGCUGAUGGACUGCCAAAAAGUAUUUUGCGACAUCUUUUGGUUCUGGAUAGUAGUGAGCAGCCAAGUGACUGUGUCUGAAACACCAGUGUAUUUUCAGGGAAUGUCCCUAACUGCGUCUUGCCCGCGCCGGGGGCUGGGGACUCUCUCUGCUGGACUUGGGACUGGCCUCUGCCCCCAGCACGCUGUAUUCUGCAGGACCGCCUCCUUCCUGCCCCUAACAACAACCACAGUGUUGCUGAAAUUGGAGAAAACUGGGGAGGGCGCAACCCCCCCCAGGCGCGGGGAAGCAUGUGGUACCGCCUCAGCCAGUGCCCCUCAGCCUGGCCACAGUCGCCUCUCCUCGGGGACCCCUCAGCAGAAAGGGACAGCCUGUCCUUAGAGGACUGGAAAUUGUCAAUAUUUGAUAAAAUGAUACCCUUUUCUACAUGGUGGGUCAGCUUUUUUUUUUUUUUUUUUAACUUUCUUUCUCAGCAUUCUCUUUGGAGUUCAACCUAGCGCCCAUGAGCCAGGCUGAGGAAGCUGAGUGAGAAGCCAGGUGGGCGGGACUUGUUCCCAGGAAGGCCGGGUGGGGAGGAAGCCUAGAGGGAACCCCAGGAAGGGCAAAUCCAGGCAAAUCUGCAGGAAUGCUCUGCCAUGGGAGCAGCUCCUCCCUUGCCACGGCCACCUUCUCUAGCACUGCAAGGUCCACAGGGCAUUGCUUUCCUUUCUAGGCGGUGGCAGUCAGGGAACAGACUGAGGUAGGUGUAGGGGGGUCUAGGCCUUCGUGGAGCACCCCAGGGAGUUAGUAGGCCCCGGGGAGACAGAGUCUGCACAGGCCCUUUCUGGGGCCACCUCCAUCCACGAGGAGCAGCCUGAGCCUUGGUGGCCGAACCUUGACCGUCCCGGAGCACAGCUUCAGGGCAGGGAACCGGAGCCCCUGGGGGGCCUCACGGGUGUGACGAGGCCCUUCAUUGCAGGCAGGUGGGCCAAUGGGAGCCCUCACCCACGCAAGCCGAGACACCACCCAGAGUGCAGGCUGCCUGGCCCCUUCUGGCACGGCCAGCUCCACACCCCCUGCCUAGGGUAUGUGUGGUCCUAAGGGCUAGGAGCUUCCCCUACUAACAUCUCCCAGAAAAAGCAGUUAAGCCCCUCAGGGCACAGCAAGGUUAGACACAGCCCCCAUCCCCAGAUCAGGACUCCAUCUUGCUAAGUGGCAUCACCGUCACCAGCCUCCCCUUAUUUAAAAGCAGCGACUGGUGUUGCCGCAGGUACCUGGUCUACGAAGACGCAGGCAUCCCUCUCCCACCGUCCACCUCCCCGGGGGCCGCUGACAGCACAGUCGCCUGGGUGCACGCUUGUGGGGGCAGCAGGAACGGGGCUGUCGGCUCUCAGGGGAUCUGGCUGCAGCCAGGGCGAGGGCCUGGCCCUUCCUUCCAGCUCCUUCCGGCUCCUUCCAGCUGAAGGGCAGGAAGCUCUGGCCGCUUAGCUUCUAGGGUUCCAUCUCCCUAGAAAGGUGCCCACGCCCAGGGCAUCAGUCAGUAGCGGCAGCAGCAGCAGACUCGGGGCUUUCCCAGGGUGGCGCAGCCACCCCAGCUGCAUGUCACCUCAGCUCUCCAUCUUAUUGCCAUUUUGUAGAUGAGGAAGCUGAGACCAGAAAGGCUAAGACCCAUGCCCCAGGCACCACACCCAUCUCUUGGGGGCUGGGCACCUGCUACCCGAGGCCACCUCCUGAAGCCCCCACUCUUCCCCCAUGUUCCACUUCAGGAGCCGCGGGGGCCCAUCCUGACACCCGGGGUUCCUCAGCCCAGCGCAGAUGUGCUUCAGUUCCAGAGGGCUUGUUGAUUUGUUUCUUAGGUACGUUACCUGUCCACCCUGAGUCCAGUGAGGCUGUCCCAAGAGCCCCUGUAGUGUGCUCCUGGGAAGGGCUGGGGGGGCUGGGGGGGCUGGGAGAGGCCCAGGGGCAGCUGUCACUGGAACCCCAGCCAGAUGUCCAAGGAAGCCGGCCAGAACACGGAGCAGCCAGAUGGCCCCAGCUGCACCUGUCUAGGGAGCCCAUGCAGCCUCCUUGCACUGGAGAAGCAGCUGUGAAAGUAGACAGAGUUGAGACUUCGCCGUGGUCAGGAGAAAAUGCAAAUUCCCAGGAACAAGAAUCCUUUAAGUGAUAUGUUUUUAUAAAACUAAACAAAUCAACAAAUAAAUCUUGAAGGCGGAUGGUUUUCCCAGCAGUGCAGGGGUUGGAGGGAGGCUGCUGGCACUCCUGGGGCCAAGGGGGACAGGCAGUGGUCCUGAGUCUGCUCAGAGAGGCAAGGCAGAAGGAGCUCGCCAGGCAGGUCAGCUCACAUCUGUCCAAGUCGCUCUGGUCAGAAACAGCGACUCUCCCCCAUUCCCCCAGCGUUCCCACCAGGCCUGGGCUGCUGGGAAGCCCUUGCUGUACCCAGGAGCCCGACCCGCAGUAUCCUGGCACAGAGCCACUUGUCACUCAGAACAGUCAGUGUCUCCAACGCACAAACAUCCACUCCUCUGUUACCAGUUAAAGCACUUUAAUGCUUUAAGGUGAAAACGAAAUCCCAUCCGUGUUUUUCGUGUAAGAUCGUGCUUCUCCGAGCAGUAUUAAUGGACGCCCUCCAAUGACAUAACAACUGUUUUUGGUAAUGUAAUCUUGGGAAAAUGUGUUAUUUUUUUAGCUGUGUUUCAGUGGGGAUUUUUGUUUUUGUAACAUAAUAAAGUGUAUGUUCCAAUGA